CCUCUUCUCCCUCCUCCGCAGGCACACCAAAAUGAAGACAGCCACCAAUAUUUACAUCUUUAACCUGGCCCUGGCCGACACUCUGGUCCUGCUGACGCUGCCCUUCCAGGGCACGGACAUCCUCCUGGGCUUCUGGCCGUUUGGGAAUGCGCUGUGCAAGACAGUCAUUGCCAUUGACUACUACAACAUGUUCACCAGCACCUUCACCCUAACUGCCAUGAGUGUGGAUCGCUAUGUAGCCAUCUGCCACCCCAUCCGUGCCCUCGACGUCCGCACGUCCAGCAAAGCCCAGGCUGUCAAUGUGGCCAUCUGGGCCCUGGCCUCUGUUGUCGGUGUUCCCGUUGCCAUCAUGGGCUCGGCACAGGUCGAGGAUGAAGAGAUCGAGUGCCUGGUGGAGAUCCCUACCCCUCAGGAUUACUGGGGCCCGGUGUUUGCCAUCUGCAUCUUCCUCUUCUCCUUCAUCGUCCCCGUGCUCGUCAUCUCUGUCUGCUACAGCCUCAUGAUCCGGCGGCUCCGUGGAGUCCGCCUGCUCUCGGGCUCCCGAGAGAAGGACCGGAACCUGCGGCGCAUCACUCGGCUGGUGCUGGUGGUAGUGGCUGUGUUCGUGGGCUGCUGGACGCCUGUCCAGGUCUUCGUGCUGGCCCAAGGGCUGGGGGUUCAGCCGAGCAGCGAGACUGCCGUGGCCAUUCUGCGCUUCUGCACGGCCCUGGGCUACGUCAACAGCUGCCUCAACCCCAUCCUCUACGCCUUCCUGGAUGAGAACUUCAAGGCCUGCUUCCGCAAGUUCUGCUGUGCAUCUGCCCUGCGCCGGGACGUGCAGGUGUCUGACCGCGUGCGCAGCAUUGCCAAGGACGUGGCCCUGGCCUGCAAGACCUCUGAGACGGUACCGCGGCCCGCAUGACUAGGCGUGGACCUGCCCAUGGUGCCUGUCAGCCCGCAGAGCCCAUCUACGCCCAACACAGAGCUCACACAGGUCACUGCUCUCUAGGCGGACACACCCUGGGCCCUGAGCAUCCAGAGCCUGGGAUGGGCUUUUCCCUGUGGGCCAGGGAUGCUCGGUCCCAGAGGAGGACCUAGUGACAUCAUGGGACAGGUCAAAGCAUUAGGGCCACCUCCAUGGCCCCAGACAGACUAAAGCUGCCCUCCUGGUGCAGGGCCGAGGGGACACAAGGACCUACCUGGAAGCAGCUGACAUGCUGGUGGACGGCCGUGACUGGAGCCCGUGCCCCUCCCUCCCCGUGCUUCAUGUGACUCUUGGCCUCUCUGCUGCUGCGUUGGCAGAACCCUGGGUGGGCAGGCACCCGGAGGAGGAGCAGCAGCUGUGUCAUCCUGUGCCCCCCAUGUGCUGUGUGCUGUUUGCAUGGCAGGGCUCCAGCUGCCUUCAGCCCUGUGACGUCUCCUCAGGGCAGCUGGACAGGCUUGGCACUGCCCGGGAAGUGCAGCAGGCAGCUUUUCUUUGGGGUGGGACUUGCCCUGAGCUUGGAGCUGCCACCUGGAGGACUUGCCUGUUCCGACUCCACCUGUGCAGCCGGGGCCACCCCAGGAGAAAGUGUCCAGGUGGGGGCUGGCAGUCCCUGGCUGCAGACCCCGAGCUGGCCCUGGGCCAGCCGCACCUCUGAAGGUUUUCUGUGUGCUGCACGGUGCAGGCCUCAUCCCUGACUGCAGCUUGACUCUGGGCCCAACCCCCAUUUCCCUUCAGGAGACCAGCGAGAGGCCCUGGCCCAUUCCCUCCAGCGGUGCAAUGAACUAUCAUGCUGUGGACCGUCAACCCAGCCCUGCUUCUCAGUGUGGGGCAGGUGUCUCAGGACGAAGGCGCCGCGUGACCACAUGGGCAGCUCUGUUCACAAAGUGGAGGCCUCGUUUUCCUGGUCUUGACUGCUCUGUUUGGGUGGGAGAAGAUUCUCUGGGGGUCCCCACAUCCUCCCAAGGCUCCCCUCACAGCCUCUCCUUUGCUUGAAGCCAGAGGUCAGUGGCCGUGCUGUGUUGCGGGGGAAGCUGUGUGGAAGGAGAAGCUGGUGGCCACAGCAGAGUCCUGCUCUGGGGACGCCUGCUUCAUUUACAAGCCUCAAGAUGGCUCUGUGUAGGGCCUGAGCUUGCUGCCCAACGGGAGGAUGGCUUCACAGCAGAGCCAGCAUGAGGGGUGGGGCCUGGCAGGGCUUGCUUGAGCCAAACUGCAAAGGCUGUGGUGGCUGUGAGGACACUGCGGGGGUUGGGGGGGGGGCGUCUGUACCUCAGGGGAUGCCCCGCUGUGGUCACCCAGAGAAUCACCCUUCCUGGUCUACAGAUGGAAGCUGCAGGUUGGUGACUUUGCAAAUGCACUUCCUACAGAUGAACUAUUAAAAGACCUGCAACAUUGAAAAAACUCAUUUUUUCCACCAAAACCUUGGCCAGGUAACCUACCUUAGGCACCUGCAAAGAACAGGAAGUGAUGGCUGUCUCGCAACAGAGCCUGGGCUGCUCCUCCUGCUCUGGGGAGUCUAGGCCGUGGGGACUGUUCUGGGGAGGCUCAUGCUGUCUCCAUGACGUCUGUGGCAGGAGUCCCUGAGGACGGGAGCUGCCUAGCUACAGUUUUCUUGCCAAGGCGAGGUGUUUUGUGAAUCUGUGCUGAUGUAAUGUGCACCUUCACGUAUUUAUGCAUGUGGCAAGCGUUACUUCCUGUGCACGUAGCCAGCCCUGGGUCUGUCUCUGGGGUAAUGAAAAAGGACCCUAAUAAACACCUGCUCACUGGCUGGGUA